AGUGAGCCCUAAGAGGUCAUAUAGAGAGCAGCAUUUCCUCUCCAGGCCGAGAUGAGGGCUGAGGGCGUUUGGAGGGAAGCGCUCUGCCUACUGCCGGGAGGUGACACCCGCGAGGCCGACCGUCCCCCGAAGCCCCCGCAAGUCCAGACUGGGGGACCUCGGAGAUCCACGAGAUUGCCAGAGAAGGAAAUUGAGGCCCAAGAAGCUGCAUGACUUAGCCAAGUUCACGGAGUAGAACCCGGGAUUGGAGCCCGGGACAUUGAAAUGAAGGCGUCUUGCAUUGCAGCUCCGUUGCAGCGCAGAGGCGCAGGAAGGCAGACUACCACGAGCCUCGGGCUGCGGCCUCGCCCUCCUGGUCGAGCCUCCUGCCCUCCAACCCUCUGCUCCCGUUUCUCCCUCUGGUUCAUAGCCCGCGGGACAGAGCAGCCCUGGAUUGGGAGGCUCCUCAGGUCUCAGGCUCAGGUGCAGAAGCAGAGCCCCUAACUGGAAGGCUCGGAGGUGGGCCGGUGAGGCAAGCAAGCCCUGUGGGGGGUUGAGGACAGCUUGGGUUGGAUGUCCCUCACUGCAGCCUGUCCGUGGAUGUCUCUGCCUUAAGGGAAUUGGAGGUGGAACCAUCCAGUCUUGAAGGUCAACGGAGCGUGAAGAGAGGAGCGUGCAGCUUGAGCACUACAGAUAGGAGCGUCCCUUGCUCCUGCCAGGCAGCCCCUCCAUAGGGGCAGUCCUGUGCUGCUGUGCCUCGGUACCCGCACAAGGUGUCUGGGGACCGCCCGGACCCCCCCUUCCAUCGGCGGCAGCGCCACCUGGCGGCCAUGGUGCGGUGGUGUGGGAGGAGCUGGGCCCGGGCUGGGCACUGAGCCCACCGGAGCUGCAGGCGUCUGCAGAGCCUUGCACCGAGUUUCCCCGCGAGGGCGGGCGGGAGGAGUCCCAGGCGGGAAUGUGAUCCCCAGGGGGCCGGGGAGGGCCCUGGGGAGGAGCCUGGCCUGGGGAAGCCGGACUUCCGUGACACAACAGACACAAAAGACAAAGUCCAUUUGGAUGGAAGUGGGAGCAGGGCGAGACGGGCCAUUUUCACUCUGUGGUCAAAGGAAAUGACUGGUCUGACUCGGUCUGGGAGCGGGGCACCCAGGGUCUAAGGAUAACUCUGGGGCCAUGACAGCCAUGAGUCUCACAGAGGACCCCGAGACUUCUGUGCUGCGAGUAACCGGACUUGUUCUGAGACCUUUGCCCUAGAGGAUGGCCAAGGGGCUCCUGGUGACCUAUGCCCUCUGGGCUGUGGGGGGCCCUGCUGGGCUCCACCACCUGUACCUGGGAAGGGACAGCCACGCCCUGCUCUGGAUGCUGACCCUGGGGGGAGGUGGGCUGGGCUGGCUCUGGGAGUUCUGGAAGCUCCCAAGCUUUGUAGCUCAGGCCAACAGAGCCCAGGGACAGAGGCAGAGCCCCAGAGGGGUGACACCCCCUCUGAGUCCCAUUCGCUUUGCUGCCCAGGUGAUAGUUGGCAUCUAUUUUGGCCUUGUGGCACUGAUUAGCCUUUCUUCCAUGGUCAACUUCUAUAUUGUGGCCCUCCCACUGGCAGUUGGCUUAGGGGUCUUGCUGGUGGCUGCUGUUGGCAACCAGACCUCAGACUUUAAGAACACUCUGGGGUCAGCAUUUCUCACUUCACCUAUCUUCUAUGGCCGCCCCAUAGCCAUACUGCCCAUUAGCGUGGCCGCCAGCAUUACAGCUCAGAGGCAUCGCCGCUACAAAGCUUUGGUGGCAUCAGAGCCGCUCAGUGUGCGGCUCUAUCGUCUGGGCUUGGCUUACCUUGCUUUCACAGGCCCACUGGCAUACAGUGCCCUCUGCAACACAGCUGCCACCCUCAGCUAUGUGGCAGAAACCUUUGGCUCCUUCUUGAAUUGGUUCAGCUUCUUCCCCCUUCUUGGCCGCCUCAUGGAGUUUGUCCUCCUUCUGCCUUACCGGAUCUGGAGGCUACUGAUGGGGGAGACUGGCUUCAACAGCAGCUGCUUUCAGGAGUGGGCGAAGCUCUAUGAGUUUGUUCACAGUUUUCAGGAUGAGAAGCGUCAGCUGGCUUACCAGGUGCUGGAAGGAUAUUCUGGCUUCUUUGGAUAUCUGUGUACAAUGGGCAAAGGUUACAGAUGCUGCUGGAAUUCUAACCUGAGCUGCUGGACCUUUCCCACGGGUUUUGGGCCUCUCAGAAGGGGCAACAAAUGAAGAAAUACAUCGGAGUUACCAGGAGCUAGUGAAGGUCUGGCACCCAGACCACAACCUGGACCAGACAGAGGAGGCACAGAGGCACUUCCUGGAGAUCCAGGCUGCGUAUGAAGUCCUGAGUCAACCCAGGAAGCCCUGGGGAUCCCGGAGGUGAAAAGAAACUUCCCCCUGAGGACUGACUCUUCCUAGCAGAGCUGGGCAACUUGUCCCAAAUCUAGCUUUGCCCACGAAUGGCAUCCCAACAGAGUUAAAGAAACUGCUUGCAGGGGCUGGGCGUGGUGGCUCAUGCCUGUAAUCCCAGCACUUUGGGAGGCCGAGGCGGGCAGAUCACGAGGUCAGGAGUUCGAGACCAGCAGCCUGGCCAAUAUAGUGAAACUUCGUCUCUACUAAAAAUACAAAAAAUUAGCCAGGAGUGGUGGCAGGCACCUGUAGUCCCAGCUACUUGGGAGGCUGAGGCAGGAGAAUCACCUGAACCUGAGAGGCGGAGGUUGCAGUGAGCCGAGAUCACGCCACUGCACUCCAGCCUGGGCAACAAGAGUGAAACUCCGUCUCAAAAAAAAAAAAAAGAAAGAAAAACUGCUUGCAGGGGACAUGAGAAAACAAUGGGGUGAGAAAAGGUUGUGGUAGAAGGAUGUGUUUAUAUUCUGAAUUUCUGAAUUCUUGGCUAUUGCAUUCUUGACAAUUUUUCUUAAAACCAGAGAGUGAAAGGCAUAUUAUAAAACAAUCAAAUAUCUUUUAGAGUAUGGACAACUAUUAUAUAUCAAUAAAAAAUUAAUUAGAAAAAAUAUAUCUUUUAGAGAACACACCACCUUAUCCCACCCAUGAUAUAUUGAUGUGUGAUGGAGAAAGAUUAUUUAACUAUUUUUUUAAAUGUGUAAAGCAGCAGGGCAUAGUGGCUUACGCCUGUAAUCCCAACACUUUGGGAAGCUGAGGUGGGAGGAUCACCUUAGGUCAGGAGUUCAAGACCAGCCUGGCCAACCAACAUGGUGAAACCCCAUCUCUACUAAAAAUACAAAACUUAGCCAGCCAUGGUGGCACAUGCCUGUAGCCCCAGCUAGUCGGGAGGCUGAGGCAGGAAAAUCACUUGAGCCUGGGAGGUGGAGGUUGCAGUCAACUGAGAUUGAGCCACUGCACUGUACUCCAGCCUGGGCGGCAGAGCUAGAUUCUGUCUCAAAAAUUAAAUAAAUAAAUAAGUAAGUAAAUAAAUAAAUAAAUAAAUGUAUAAAGCACUAUGUUAGGAGAUUGAAGGAAAAAUAUGAAGGUUCUAGUAUUCACAAGCUGUCCUGUGAUAAGAGAGAUUUGAUCUUUUCUGUAGAUGGGGUGAGACUAGGAUUAAAUUUCAAAAUUUGAGAAAAAUAUUUUCAUUCCAUUUAUGGGAGAACUUUCUAGCAGCUACACUUUCUCCAAAAGGGAACAAGCUACUGUGGAGUGGGGGGUAGUUCUUCCUCCUCUGCUUAGAGGAGAAUUUUUGGAGAGCUCUCAGACUUUACAUAGGUGAUUGGACUGGCUGACUUCUCAGGUCUUCCCAGUAUUUGAGGUCUGAUUCUGGGCUACAUACCCUACUCCUAGAAGCAUACAAUCUGAUGGGAGAUAAUGACACAGGUACACAGAUAUCAAAGCCCUUGUUCAGUGUUUUGAACUAAAUGUCAUAAGAGCUGUAAAUAGUGUAUUGGCACAUUGGAGGAGGGACAGAUAACAUUGUUUUAUGGGGACUCAGAAAGAUUCAUUAUUUUAUAUGUCAUAUGUCCCUUUGGGGACUUUGGGAAACCCUAGGGAACCAGCGGCUAGAGCAUCUCAAGGGGGCCUUAUUCAAUUCUAGGUAACUAGCCAGGUGUGAAAGAAAGGGCCCAGGGUGUCUCACUUUGCAGAGGAAGAUUGGAGACCAGGAACAUGAUUUUAAAUUAUGUGCCUUUACUGCAGCUUUCUUGCUCUCUUUGUGUGUGUGCAUUCUUUCCAUUUUUUUCUUCUUUCUGGAUGUUAAAUCUGAGUAAUAUAUAUCAUUUUUAAAGUGGAAUUAUGACCAGGCAUGGUGCCUCUUGCCUAUAAUCCUAGCACUUUGGCAAGCCAAGGCAGGAAGAUUGCUUGAGCCCAGGAGUUCAACACCAGCCUGGGCAACAUGGCAAAACUCCAUCUCUACAAAAAGUACAAAAAUGAGCCAGGUGUUGUGGGGUGCGCCUGUAGUCCCAGCUAAGGAGGCUGAGAUUGGGAGGAUCACUUGAACCCAAAAGGUGGAGGCUGCAGUGAGCUGAGAUCGUACCACUACACUCCAGCCUGAGUGACACAGUGACAGCCUGUCUCAAAAAUAUAAAAAUAAAUAAAUAAAUAAAGUGGAAUUAUGUUGA